AUCACUCGCGGCAUUGGAGUCAAGAUGGAGGAGUACGCGCGAGAGCCUUGCCCAUGGCGAAUUGUGGAUGACUGUGGUGGGGCCUUUACGAUGGGUACCAUUGGUGGUGGUAUCUUUCAAGCAAUCAAAGGUUUUCGCAAUUCUCCAGUGGGAGUAAACCACAGACUACGAGGGAGUUUGACAGCUAUUAAAACCAGGGCUCCACAGUUAGGAGGUAGCUUUGCAGUUUGGGGAGGGCUGUUUUCCAUGAUUGACUGUAGUAUGGUUCAAGUCAGAGGAAAGGAAGAUCCCUGGAACUCCAUCACAAGUGGUGCCUUAACGGGAGCCAUACUGGCAGCAAGAAAUGGACCAGUGGCCAUGGUUGGGUCAGCCGCAAUGGGUGGCAUUCUCCUAGCUUUAAUUGAAGGAGCUGGUAUCUUGUUGACAAGAUUUGCCUCUGCACAGUUUCCCAAUGGUCCUCAGUUUGCAGAAGACCCCUCCCAGUUGCCUUCAACUCAGUUACCUUCCUCACCUUUUGGAGACUAUCGACAAUAUCAGUAGGACUUCUUUCCUAGGAUUUCUUUAACAGAACGAGUUGUGGUUCGAGAAGGAUUUCAGAAGAUCAAGUUACAGUCUGUUUUUAAAACCAUAGGUGGGACAGCUAUGGCCAAUAGGCUAUAAAGAGACAUUUAGCACUUUUUUCUAUUUAAAGGAACAAGCGGGGAAGGGUGCUAAAAGAUAAUACGUUUAUUUAUUCACACUUGAAUUGCAUUUGUGAUCAAAAUAAAUGUUUAAAUCGCUAAAGGAAAAUACAGUAAGUGCUUGAAAGAUGAAGGACCAAAAGGCCAAAAAACAGUGAAAUAUGAUCAUCAUCUCCUUGCGGACUUCUCUGCCUGGUUUUGUGUGUUCUGUUAUUCAAACAAUAAAAAGCUGGUGGAACUUACUCUUUCUUUUAAGAUAAGUUGUAGACUUCGAUGUUUCAUGCUCAUGUACUUCAAAUAAUGCAUGUUUUAUAGUUAGUCCCUCAUCACUUGAAGUGACUUCUGAGAAUUAUGCAGAGUCAACAUGGAUCAUUUCACAGUGAGAUGCUUUAUGGAUUGAAGGAUAUGGUAAAAUGUUUAUAGUUUACUUUGAAAGUAAAAUAUACUAUGUCUUGGUUUUGAGGAUAUUGGAUACAAAACUCUCUUCCUUUAGGGCUACUGAGUCUUGAUUCCUGAUCAUCAGAAAUUUCACCAGAAACAACUUGCUUCCAAUAUACCCAAUUCUAUAUGAAGAAUUCAUGGAGAGUGUACUGGCACUGGAAGAGUUUAGUGUUUCUUGUAUGCUUGAAAAUAAAGUAUGUACUGUUUUGAAUGUGUUCCAAGUCCUCUGCAUAAACGAUGUAUUUUGGGGUCUGGUUGGGCCUGGAAAAUGGAUGAGCACUUCAGAACAGGUCAUUUUCCUGAUAUUGGAAGUGACAUGUGGCCCUAUAGGAGGCAUGAUGUUAGUUAAUUACACAUUUGCCUACAUCUGUGGGAAAUGGAGAACAAAGCCAUGUGGGUACUGUAAACACACGUUUAUCUUUUGGCCCAAUGCCAUACAUAUGGUAGGCAUUUAAUUACUGAUUGUGUUUGGAUAAUUUGGGAAUUUUCGACUGUGGUAAAAUAUACAUAAAAUAAUACUUAUUAACCA